CGGGCGGAGCGGGCCUCGGGUCUGCGGAGGGUGGACGCGCGCUCUCCCUGUCUUUGGAGGGAGGGUUUCCUGUGGUCGGGAGGCGAGGCAGCCAGGGCAGGAUUGGGCUCCUGACCUGCAGGCCACGGGCGAGCUCUCUCUAGGGCCCUGAUUUGCCCGAAGAAGGCGCUUGGUGAAGGUGAAAGGUUUACGCAUCCAAGUAGCUAGAACCUCUUUCCAGAACUUCUGCUGAUGCACUUAGUCUUGCAGCCAUUGAUUAUUAUAGCUCAGCAAAGUUCAGUUCAACUUUCGGAAGAAGGAUGUGAGCUGGAAUGGGCAGGGUCAAGAUUUGACAGGAAAAGACACUUCACUGGAGGUAUCUGCGAGAGUCCUGGGUUGGAGGGAAGGAGUACUGGUUAUAAAUAAGGAAAUGAUGUCUUCAUCACUUCCUAAACACAUACAUGUCAUUCCCUACCAUCUCCACCCUCUGUUUAUUCAGAGCUGCACCAACCAUGUUCAUCACCUCACCUGGGAUUUACUGAGUUUACCCCUUACAGAGCUACACGAUAGGGGUAAAGGAAAGACUAAAAACCAAUUUAUCUUAUAUUAAAAUUACGACUUAGUAAAUAUUUUUUUCAGUAAUGCAGUUUGCUAGUGACAGAUCCAAUAACUGAAUUCUGGUCCUUUGAGUACCAGGUCAGGGCUUUUGUCAUCUACCACAUUUACGUUACCUACCACAAGAAGUUUCUUAGUAAAAGGUCCUCUUGUGAAACUGCAGCUAAGGGAAACCAAACUGUCAAAAAGACAAACACCUUAAAGCACUUUCAUUCAUUCUCUCUGGAUUCUGUCAUCUCAAGUGGCUAAACACAUUAGUAGGAAAACAGGUAAGUGACAUAAUAUCAUUUUCCUAUUCCAAGAAAUCUUUUAAUCCUAGAGUCCAUUUUAAUGCCAAAAUAGUGUUCCAGGCUUUGUAUAUACUAACUUUCGUUGACCUAGUCUCCUAUUAAUUGGACUCAGACGUUUUCAAUUUUUUUCAAAGGAGGCAUAGAUUGACAGUAAUUCAGUAGAAAACAUUUGUUGACACUCACUCAGUAAGAAAAGCUCUAUGAGACCAUUCUAGAACUAUAAAUGGACAAGUGAACGUUUCCUCAACAUGUUGCUUCCUGAACCAGACUGGUCAAAGGGCCAUGUUUUUAAAUGGGUGUGUGGCUUUGUAGGUAAUUGUAGAGCUGCUGUGUGAGCCAAAUCGCUCAUGAUUCCAUUCGCCAUUCUUCCUUACCCAGCUCUGCUUUCAACACUCUUGGCCCUUUCUCAAGAGAACAUGAAAAUGAAAAAAUUUCAGGUAAGUUGCUCAGGGAUUUACUUCUCACAUUAUACAGUGAAUUUCAAGAGGUUUAGAGUAGUUUGCAGAUGAAACGAAAUGUAUAAAAUUCAGCAUCAGAGAAGAGUAUUCGAUCAAUACUGGAAAAGUGGACAUAGAUAUACAGAAAUCAUAUAUUCCUAUAGAGUUACUCAAAUGGUUCCAGAAAGGCCCAGACAAUAUGAGAUAGCCCUUACACUGGAUUUUUGUGUGGUUUUCCCAUCAUUUAUAUCUAAAAAUUUUCUUGGAUGAUCUUUGAGUAAGUGAAGUAGAGACAGUUCUGCCAAAAACAGCUGAGAAAGAAAUGGUAUGGGUUUCCUGUGACUUCUAUACCCAGGCAGAGCACAGUAAUUACAGGGAACCAAUCCAGUGUCAUCCGAACAGGCAGCAUUCUGAUGGUUCUCUGUGAUGUCUAUGAUCCAGUGAUAAGACCUAGAAUAAAUGGAUAAAACCUAUAACAAAUAAAAUAGUGUUCCUCAAAUAAUGCCCCAUAACUUUAUUUCAGCUAUACUUAUAAAACAAGUUCUAGAGGGAACAAUUCAAUAUUAUAUUCUGUAGGUAAAACUUCUUCAUGUGCCUGUCUCAUUUCAACCCACUUGAUACAGUCUGGUGUCUGCCCCCACCACUCUGAUGGAUCUGUUCUGGAAAAAUUUAGCAGUAACCUAAAUAUUUUCAAACCCAAUGAGUAUCUUUCAGUUCAUACUUUACCAAACUCUUUGUUGCAUUUGACAGUAUGACUGCCCCCUCCCUAAUAGGCACCUCUGAUAAUGUCUGUGGUAUCACUCACAUGAUUCUCUUUGUAGCUCUGUAAUCAUGUCUUUUUUUUUUUUUUUUAAUUGAGAUGAGGUCUCACUAUGUUGCCCAGGCUGGUCUCGAACUCCUGGGUUCAAGUGAUCCUCCCACCUUGGCCUCCCAAAGUGCACUGAUUACAGCUGUGAGCUGCCACACCCAGCUUGUAAUCAUGUCUUCUUUAUAUCUUUUAUACAAUCUUUUGUUUCAUGAACAUUGCUAUGCCAUUGUUAGCCCAUUAUUCUUUCUGAUUUUUUUUCAUGCCCUUUGUGGUUUUAACUUGUGAGUCUUUAUGCUCUGAGGUAUUUCUGCCUCUGAGGACCUCAGCUUGAGAUUCUUGCUGAACAUCUCUGUAAGGAUGUCCAGAAGGCACAUGGAGUCCUCAUAUCCAACAUGGAAAUAAUACUUACAACUUGCUCAAUGUGCUGCUGCUUCUUUUUUCCCUAUCAGUGCUGCUUCCAUCUGACCAGCGAGACAAGCCAGAAAAUGAAGGCCAUCUUUUUUUUUUUUUUUUUUUGAAAUGGGCUCUCACUCUAUCACCCAGGCUGGAGUGCAGUGGCACGAUCUCAGCUCACUGCAAACUCUGCCUCCCGGGUUCACACCAUUCUCCUGCCUCAGCCUCCCAGGUUCACACCAUUCUCCUGCCUCAGCCUCCCGAGUAGCUGGGACUACAGGCACCCGCCACCACGCCUGGCUAAUUUUUUGUAUUUUUUAGUAGAGACGGGGUUUCGCCAUGUUAGCCAGGAUGGUCUCAAUCUCCUGACCUCGUGAUCCUCCUGCCUCGGCCUCACUAAGUGCUGGGAUUACAGGCGUGAGCCAUCGCGCCCGGCCUGAAGUCCAUCUUAAUUCUCCUUUUCCUCACGUCCUACCAUACCUGUUUGUCGAGCUUGCUAAUGUUGUCACAUAAACAUUUCUUGAAUUUGUCCUUUCACUUCCAUCUCCUCCUCUCCUGCCUCAGUUUCUCGUGGGUUGUCAUAAUAUUAGUAGCUUUCUCAGCAGUCUGCUUGGCCCCUUCCUCUUCCCACCUCAAGGCUGUUCUUCACACUGACCAAUUCCUCCAAAAUGCCAACGUGAUCAUGUCUUAAUACAGAAAUGACUUAAGAGGUUCCACGCCACUUGCAGAAUACAAGUUCAGCAUCCUUGGUAUGACCUGUAAGGCUAUGUAUGUCAUGACCGUUUCCUGCCUCUUCUCAGUUCCUACCACUCUGGACCUUUCAUUCAACAACUGUAUAUUGAUCAAACAAUUGUGUGUGAUACGCUAUGCUAGAUGGUCUACAUUCAGCUUGAAUGAAGGAGAUACUGUCUCUGUCCUCAUGGAGCUCAUGUGCUAGUGAAAGAGAAAGAUAUUACACAAGCAAUUCAAACUGUGCUGAGGUGGUUCUCAACUCUGCCAGACCCAUAUCUUUUUACAGAACAUACUUUCUUAGGAGCUAUAUUGGGAUGCAAACCUUCCAUAUUCUGCCAUCCCCUUUAUCUCUCUUAGUUAAUGCCACCCACCCACACCAGGCUGCCUCCUGUUUUAGACUUGGAUGAAACCACACACCAUGAGGUGUGGUACCAGCUUCCUGAGGGGCCAGAUGGUGGAGCCAGAUGAUGCAACCUGGAAGUGUGCGCAAGUUAACUCACCGUGGGUGAACCUUGAAUGAAGGGAAAUGGAAAAUGAGAAGGAGAGAUGGGGUUUUGCCGUGUUGCCCAGACUGAUCUUGAGCUUCUGAGCUCCAGCGAUCAGCCUACCUCAACCUCUCAGAGUGCUGGGAUUAUAGGUGUGCGCCACCACACCUGGCCAUGUGUGUUUUCUUACAUCUCCUUUCUUACAUAAAAGGUAAUAUAUUAUAGAUAUUCUUUAAUACUUUGCUUUUUUCACUUCAUAUCAGUUCAUGGAGACCUUCCUCAUUAUUUAUGCUUUCAAAUAUUGCUUCUGAUCACUGUGGUAUCUCUCCUGUGAGCUCCAGAACCAUAUAUCAAACUGCCAGCUAGAUAUCUGUACUUCUUUACUCAACAGACACUUCAAGCACAGCAUGGUAAAGAUCAGUGCCUUCAUUUCCUAUGCUCGAUUCUCUUUUUUGUUUUGUUUUCCUAAUCUCCACAUAUACUACUAGCGUCAGCCCAGCUGAUCAUGUGAAAUAAUAUGCACAUUACAUCUACUGCACAUCAAGUAGUGGUCAACUCUCCUUGCCUCCCGUUAUGUAGGACUGAUUCUCUCCUUCCCAUUUCCCAGGAACUACCUGUGCUCAUGUCCUGUAGUAGUGUCUUAGUUUUCUUCCCUUCUAAUUUGACCUUUAAGCCAGUUUCCAUUUUUCUAGAGUAGGGGACAGCAAAUGUUUUCUUUAGAGGACAAGGUCAAAAUUUUUGGCUUUGCUGGCCCUGUGGUCUCUGUUGGAUUUCCUUGGCACAGCUGUUGUGACAUGAAAGCAGUCAUAGACUGUGUGUAACAAAUGAGCGUGACCACGUUUGGCUCCCAGUGGCCUAGAUUUUGCCCACGGACUGAAGUUUGCCAACUCUUAUGCUCUAGAGCAUUGUUUCAAAAUACACAUUUGGUCACAAAUCUCCAGUCCUUGCUUACAAAUAACUCUUUAUGGAUUUCCAUUAUUUAUAACAGUGAUCUCCAAAGUGGAGGAUAGGGAGCACCCCAGCAAUUCACUGGACUUCUAUUCUUGUAUUUCAGCCAAAAGAAUGAAAAAAUAAUUAAGCUUUAUUGAUAUUAGUGUAUAGCUGGAACUCACUUGGAAAUAUACUACAAUUCCUAAGUAAAUGUACGUUAGCGUAUAUGCAAGAAUGUUUUACUGAUGUGCCGUACUAUCUAAAUUUCAAGACUACUAAUUAGAGAAAAGAGUUCCUCUAUUCUCUGACCUCUGUCCCGCUCCUCACUAACCUUUCCUGUGGAGAGAUUGUAGUUCUCGAACUCCCCAUAUGUGUUUUGUGUCUGUGUAUAUUCUUAAUGGCUACAGUCCUAUAAAACAUACUGUUUAUAUUUCAGGACUAAAAUUAUUAUGCUCUCAAGGAAGGGGUAACAAAAAUGGAGCAAGCUUUCUUCUUUUGUGAUCACCCUUCAUCUUGUGUAUAUGUCCAGCAUUGCUCUUUAAAGAUGUACAUUUCUAUUUUUGUCACCCUGUCAGAAUGUAUGCUCCUAAAGAGUAAGAUUAGUAUUUUAUGUGAUUAGUAAUCCAGGCAAUUGGAAUAGCUCCAGGACAUGGUAUAAGCUCAGCACAUUUUUAAAAUUCAUUUUAAAAAAUGAACACAGUGACAGAUUUUUAAUUUUCUGCCCUCCCACAAUUACAUCUCUCUAUAGCUUUCCAUUAGCCAUGGCAGUGGUCUUCUUAUAGUUUAUGUUACCAUACAUUUGAUAUCACUCAAUUUUGGUCACCCAAGAUUAAACAUUUUCUUUCAGAUACCAGUUUCAUUCCAGGACCUGACUGUGAACUUCACCCAAGAGGAAUGGCAGCAACUGGACCCUGCUCAGAGGCUCCUGUACAGGGAUGUGAUGCUGGAGAACUACAGCAACUUGGUCUCUGUGGGGUAUCAUGUUAGCAAACCAGAUGUGAUUUUCAAAUUGGAGCAAGGAGAAGAGCCAUGGAUAGUGGAGGAAUUCUCAAAUCAGAACUACCCAGACAUUGAUGAUGCCUUAGAGAAGAACAAGGAAAUCCAAGAUAAACAUUUGACACAAACUGUAUUCUUCAGCAACAAAACACUGAUUACAGAAAGAGAGAAUGUAUUUGGGAAAACACUUAAUCUGGGCAUGAAUAGUGUUCCCUCAAGAAAAAUGCCCUAUAAAUGUAAUCCAGGAGGAAACAGUUUGAAAACUAAUUCAGAAGUAAUUGUUGCAAAGAAAAGCAAAGAAAACAGAAAGAUUCCUGAUGGAUACAGUGGAUUUGGGAAGCAUGAGAAAAGUCAUUUGGGAAUGAAAAAAUACAGAUACAAUCCAAUGAGGAAAGCCAGCAAUCAAAACGAAAAUCUUAUUCUGCACCAGAACAUUCAGAUUUUGAAACAACCGUUUGACUAUAAUAAAUGUGGGAAAACCUUCUUCAAGAGGGCAAUUCUCAUUACACAAAAGGGGAGACAGACUGAAAGGAAACCAAAUGAAUGUAAUGAAUGUAGGAAAACCUUUUCUAAGAGAUCUACCCUCAUUGUACAUCAGAGAAUUCAUACAGGGGAGAAACCGUAUGUUUGUAGUGAUUGUAGGAAAACUUUUCGUGUGAAGACAAGCCUCACUCGACACCGAAGAAUUCAUACUGGAGAGAGACCCUAUGAAUGCAGUGAAUGCAGGAAAACCUUCAUUGACAAAUCUGCCCUUAUUGUACACCAGAAAAUUCAUGGAGGGGAGAAAUCCUAUGAGUGUAAUGAAUGUGGAAAGACCUUUUUUCGGAAGUCAGCCCUGGCUGAACAUUUCAGGUCACACACAGGGGAGAAGCCUUACGAAUGCAAGGAAUGUGGAAAUGCCUUCAGCAAGAAAUCGUAUCUUGUUGUACAUCAAAGAACUCACAGAGGAGAGAAGCCAAAUGAAUGUAAGGAAUGUGGGAAAACCUUCUUCUGUCAGUCAGCCCUUACUGCGCAUCAGAGAAUUCACACAGGGGAAAAACCCUAUGAAUGUAGUGAAUGUGAGAAAACCUUCUUUUGUCAAUCUGCCCUCAAUGUGCAUCGAAGAAGUCAUACAGGAGAGAAGCCCUAUGAAUGCAGUCAAUGUGGAAAAUUUUUAUGUACGAAAUCAGCCCUCAUUGCACAUCAGAUAACUCAUAGAGGAAAGAAGUCUUAUGAAUGUAAUGAAUGUGGGAAAUUUUUCUGCCAUAAGUCAACACUCACUAUACAUCAGAGAACACACACAGGAGAGAAACAUGGUGUGUUUAAUAAAUGUGGUAGAAUCUCCAUUGUGAAGUCAAACUGCAGUCAGUGUAAGAGAAUGAACACAAAGGAGAAUCUUUAUGAGUGUAGUGAACAUGGGCAUGCCGUCAGCAAAAACUCACACCUCAUUGUACAUCAGAGAACUAUAUGGGAGAGACCAUAUGAAUGCAAUGAAUGUGGGAGAACCUACUGCAGGAAGUCAGCCCUGACUCACCAUCAGAGAACACACACAGGACAGAGACCCUAUGAGUGUAAUGAAUGUGGGAAAACCUUCUGUCAGAAGUUCUCCUUUGUUGAACAUCAGCGAACUCACACUGGGGAGAAACCAUAUGAAUGUAAUGAAUGUGGGAAAUCCUUCUGCCAUAAGUCAGCCUUCAGAGUCCAUAGAAGAAUUCACACAGGAGAGAAACCAUAUGAAUGUAAUCAAUGUGGGAAAACCUACCGUCGCCUGUGGACUCUCACUGAACAUCAGAAAAUACACACAGGAGAGAAACCUUAUGAAUGUAACAAAUGUGAGAAAACAUUUCGCCACAAAUCAAACUUUCUUUUACAUCAGAAAUCCCACAAGGAAUAAGUUCCAACAAAGUAAUAAAUUCCAACAAAGCAACAAAUCAAAUAACUUACACAAUGCUAAACUGUGAGUAUGUAUAGAGGAGUAAAAUCUUAUAAAUGUAAUGAAUAUGGAAAAUUUUUCUGCCAUAAGUCAACCCUCAAUGUAACAUCAGAGAAAUCAUGUAGGAAAGAAAUAAUUUGUUUAAUAAAUGUAUUAUUCAUUGUGAACUAUGAAAAUAUUCAACAGCAAUUCAAAGGUUAUGCCAAAUGUGCCUCCCUUUUAAAAUAAUGAAACAAACAUUGUUUAAGUUAAAUUGUUACUUGGUUCCUCCCCACAGUGUUACUUGAUAGUGUAUGUUACGAGGUGUGAGGAUCUGACCUUCAUUUCAAAUCAAUACCAUUGUUUGAUAGUUGAGUAAGUUACAGUUUCUCAAUUUAUGGUGUAUUUUCAGAUUUGGCAGAUUUUUUGUUGUCUGCUAACUCCAUAGUCUUCUAGUAGUGGACUGUAUACCUUUAUCUGCAAAGGUGACAACUCAGGAGAACUAACCAUUGUACUCUAUGCACCCAUGGUAAUUAUACCCCAGGUGAGCAUUUUGUAAAGCUGAGCCAGUGAAAGCCCUUCCUAAGACCUUUCUAAUGGAAGAUAGGCACAGGAUAACUAGUUCAUGAUCCUGAAGCUUUCAGCUAAGUCAAGAAGACGGCAAUUGCAGUAGGAAAAACAUGGGAAAAUAAGCAUUCUUGAACAACAAAGAGAAUUUGGAUGAUGGUUGAAUCCAAAAAGUGUUUAUUUCUCUGGUUUUAGUAUUCUGUAAUAUCCACUCAACCCCAUCUACCAGUGGUUUAUGUCAAUUAGUAUGUUUUCAAAAAUCUCUUGGAUUUCCUAAUCAACAUGUUCAUUAGAGGUAUUGUUUAGAAGUCACUGAUCAAAUUCUGAGAACAAAAGGCGCCUGGGAUGCUGAUUAGGAUUACAUUAUAUGGAUAUAUAUGAUGAGGUAGGAUUGCCACUUUUAUGGGGUUAUUGGGAAAUGUUUACCUUUCAAGUUCUGAUUUCCAUGAGUGGGAUUUUCCCUAUACCCAUUCCUAGCUUCUCUGCCACAUUAUGCAUUCUGCCCCAGGCAUGAGGAAGUGGGCUUAUCUAGUUGGUAAGAUAGUGAUGGGUAACUGGGUUUGCUCAGCUGAACUCCCUCUUCAUUGUGGGCUGACCUGCAAGUAUAAUUUCUUGUCACAGAUAUUGCCUGUGAUUGGUAAAUUGGUCUAAUUCUGUCAUUCAGCUAAUUGGCCCAUUAGCUGAAUGGUCACACUAAGUUGCAUCCUCCAACUCAAUUUGAUCAGUAAUAAAAGUUUCAUCCUGCCCCCUGUCUGCUACUUAAUUUUUUAUCGUUUAGAUGGGGGGAAAUUGUGCUAUUUAUUUGGGGCCCUUCAGAGAACCCAAUAUGAACAUGAUUUAUCUAUUUAUUCAGUUUUUAUGUCCUUCAGGACAGAUAAAUGUAUGUAUACACACAUAUACAUGUGUUAAUAUAUGUAAGUAUAUACAUAUGUUUAAAUGUAUGUGUAUGUGUAUACUGAUCUUGCUCUUUUCCUGUGAAAUGUAUUAAUAGUCACUUCAAAGAUUUGGUUGCUAUUGUGAAAGAAAUUAAGUUACCUUUCACUUUGAAACUAAUAGAGUAAAGAAAAACAAAAAUACCUAA